AGUACGGUGUGUGGAGCUGGAGCACCGUGAGGAAGAAGCGAGGUUCUUUUUAAGAGUUCAGCUGCGAGAUAUCAAACAAAGAAUUACUCUGUACAAAGCCAGAACACAUAUAUCAAAGUAAUCCUGAAGUAUCAGAACAAAAUAAUAGGCUGUAACAGAGGAGGAAAUGAUUUUGAAUAGCCUCUCUCUGUGUUACCAUAAUAAGCUAAUCCUGGCCCCAAUGGUUCGGGUAGGGACUCUUCCAAUGAGGCUGCUGGCCCUGGAUUAUGGAGCGGACAUUGUUUACUGUGAGGAGCUGAUCGACCUCAAGAUGAUUCAGUGCAAGAGAGUUGUUAAUGAGGUGCUCAGCACAGUGGACUUUGUCGCCCCUGAUGAUCGAGUUGUCUUCCGCACCUGUGAAAGAGAGCAGAACAGGGUGGUCUUCCAGAUGGGGACUUCAGACGCAGAGCGAGCCCUUGCUGUGGCCAGGCUUGUAGAAAAUGAUGUGGCUGGUAUUGAUGUCAACAUGGGCUGUCCAAAACAAUAUUCCACCAAGGGAGGAAUGGGAGCUGCCCUGCUGUCAGACCCUGACAAGAUUGAGAAGAUCCUCAGCACUCUUGUUAAAGGGACACGCAGACCUGUGACCUGCAAGAUUCGCAUCCUGCCAUCGCUAGAAGAUACCCUGAGCCUUGUGAAGCGGAUAGAGAGGACUGGCAUUGCUGCCAUCGCAGUUCAUGGGAGGAAGCGGGAGGAGCGACCUCAGCAUCCUGUCAGCUGUGAAGUCAUCAAAGCCAUUGCUGAUACCCUCUCCAUUCCUGUCAUAGCCAACGGAGGAUCUCAUGACCACAUCCAACAGUAUUCGGACAUAGAGGACUUUCGACAAGCCACGGCAGCCUCUUCCGUGAUGGUGGCCCGAGCAGCCAUGUGGAACCCAUCUAUCUUCCUCAAGGAGGGUCUGCGGCCCCUGGAGGAGGUCAUGCAGAAAUACAUCAGAUACGCGGUGCAGUAUGACAACCACUACACCAACACCAAGUACUGCUUGUGCCAGAUGCUACGAGAACAGCUGGAGUCGCCCCAGGGAAGGUUGCUCCAUGCUGCCCAGUCUUCCCGGGAAAUUUGUGAGGCCUUUGGCCUUGGUGCCUUCUAUGAGGAGACCACACAGGAGCUGGAUGCCCAGCAGGCCAGGCUCUCAGCCAAGACUUCAGAGCAGACAGGGGAGCCAGCUGAAGAUACCUCUGGUGUCAUUAAGAUGGCUGUCAAGUUUGACCGGAGAGCAUACCCAGCCCAGAUCACCCCUAAGAUGUGCCUACUAGAGUGGUGCCGGAGGGAGAAGUUGGCACAGCCUGUGUAUGAAACGGUUCAACGCCCUCUAGAUCGCCUGUUCUCCUCUAUUGUCACCGUUGCUGAACAAAAGUAUCAGUCUACCUUGUGGGACAAGUCCAAGAAACUGGCGGAGCAGGCUGCAGCCAUCGUCUGUCUGCGGAGCCAGGGCCUCCCUGAGGGUCGGCUGGGUGAGGAGAGCCCUUCCUUGCACAAGCGAAAGAGGGAGGCUCCUGACCAAGACCCUGGGGGCCCCAGAGCUCAGGAGCUAGCACAACCUGGGGAUCUGUGCAAGAAGCCCUUUGUGGCCUUGGGAAGUGGUGAAGAAAGCCCCCUGGAAGGCUGGUGACUACUCUUCCUGCCUUAGUCACCCCUCCAUGGGCCUGGUGCUAAGGUGGCUGUGGAUGCCACAGCAUGAACCAGAUGCCGUUGAACAGUUUGCUGGUCUUGCCUGGCAGAAGUUAGAUGUCCUGGCAGGGGCCAUCAGCCUAGAGCAUGGACCAGGGGCCGCCCAGGGGUGGAUCCUGGCCCCUUUGGUGGAUCUGAGUGACAGGGUCAAGUUCUCUUUGAAAACAGGAGCUUUUCAGGUGGUAACUCCCCAACCUGACAUUGGUACUGUGCAAUAAAGACACCCCCUACCCUCACCCACGGCUGGCUGCUUCAGCCUUGGGCAUCUUCAUAAA